GCAGAGCUGCCCGCCUUCGGGCCCUGCGCGGGGAGGCUGGUCCCAACCUUGCGUGGGCUUCGCGUGGGCCCGGCCUCGCCGCUGCGGUCGCCCGCCUGGCAUGGCCAACUGGGUGUUCUGUAAUCGCUGCUUCCAGCCGCCCCACAGGACGUCGUGCUUCAGCCUCACCAACUGCGGGCACGUGUACUGCGACGCCUGCCUCGGCAAAGGUAAAAAGAAUGAAUGCUUGAUUUGUAAAGCUCCUUGUCGUACAGUUUUGCUUUCAAAGCAUCGCCCCUUUCCUGUGUCUGACAGCGAGUCACCAACAGCACGCCUUUACAGCUGCGUGAGGAGAGCCCCGUGGAUCCCGCACAGGGGUACCCGUGUCCGCUUGCGCCGUCGGACCUUGUGGACUCGAUUGCUCUGCACCAGGGUUGAUUUCCUCCAUUCCUUACGCCCUCUGCCAUGAUGACGUCAGACGCAGCAAAGGCCUUCAGUCACGCUACCGACGCAGAUAUCCAGGCAUUCUUCAUGAGCAUAGACAGUCUGUGUAAGAAGUACUCCAGGGAAACCUCCCAGAUUUUAGAAUUUCAAGAAAAACACAGGAAGAGAUUGUUAGCCUUCUAUAGAGAAAAGAUUUCUAGGUUGGAAGAAUCCCUUAGGAAGUCAGUGCUGCAGAUAGAACAACUACAAAGUAUGAGAUCAUCACAACAAACAGCUUUCAGCACAAUAAAAAGUUCAGUUUCAACAAAACCACACGGAUGCCUGCUGCCACCUCACUCAUCAGCCCCCGACAGACUGGAGUCGAUGGAAGUUGAUCUCUCUCCUUCUCCGAUUAGAAAAUCUGAGAUAGCAGCCGGCCCUGCGAGAAUCUCCAUGAUUAGUCCACCUCAAGAUGGACGAAUGGGGCCACAUCUAACAGCUUCUUUCUGUUUCAUCCCAUGGUUGACCUUGUCUAAGCCCCCUGUGCCCGGAGAGUGUGUCAUUUCCAGAGGUUCACCAUGUUUCUGCAUAGACGUCUGUCCUCACUGGCUGCUCCUCCUAGCGUUCAGUUCUGGAAGGCACGGGGAACUCACCAACUCUAAAACACUUCCAAUAUAUGCUGAGGUACAAAGGGCCGUCUUGUUUCCGUUCCAGCAGGCUGAGGGCACCCUGGACACGUUCAGAACACCCGCUGUGUCUGUUGUGUUUCCUCUUUGCCAAUUUGAAAGGAAAAAGUCAUUUUGAUUUGCAUUUAUGUGACUAUUAAUGAUUCUGAGUGUUUUCAAUUUAUUCCUCUGUGUUUUUUCUACAAAUUAUCUGCUUUAUUCCUUUGUCAUUUAUGUGGAAGCCCUCAGUGUGCAGGAUAUUAACCUUUUACCCAAUUUGCUUUGUAAUUUUAUAUUUGACCUUUGAAUUUUAGAGACAAUAUUUUUAUGUACUCAUAUAUAUUGUUAUUAUCCCUUUUAUUUUAUAGGUUCUCAUGCUUAGGGAGUUUUUUUUUCACAUACUUAAAUCAUUUUUUUCUAACUGGGUGGUUUUUAAAACUUUUUCUUAGAGCAGUUUUAGGUUCACAGAAAAAUUGAAAGGAAGGUACAGAUUUCCCAUAUACACCAUGACUCCACACACGCACAGCUCCCCCAUCAUCCUCAUCCUCCACCAGAGCAGUCCAUGUGUUAAAACUGAUGAUCCUACUUGAAUACAUCAUUAUCACCCAACGUCCAUGGUUUACAUUAGGGUUCACUCUAGGUGUCGAAUGUUCUAUGGGUUUGAACAAAUAUCUAGUGACAUGUGUCCCCAUCGUAGCAGCAUAUGGAAUAGUGCCACACCCUAAAAAUCCUCUGUGCGCCACCUGUUCAUCCUUCCCCCACCUCCCACCAACCCUUGACAGCCACUGAUCUUUUUACGGUCCCUUUUUCAGACUCUCCUGGAGUUGGAAUUGUACAGUAUGUGGCUUCUCAGAUUGACUCCUUUCACUUAGCAAUACACACUUAUGGUUCCCCCAUCUCUUCUCAUGGUUUGCUAGCUCAUUUUUUCAGUCACUGAAUAAUAUUCCAUUAUCUGGAUGUAUCAUAGUUCAUCCAUUCACCUACUGAAGGGCAUCUUGGUUGCUUCCAAGUUUUGGCAAUUAUGAAUUAAGCUGCUAUAGAUGUCCAUGUGCCAGGGUUUUGUGUAGACAUGUUUUCAGCUCCUUUGGGUAAAUACUAAGGAGUGUGAAUGCUGGAUCAGAUGGUGAGAGGGUGUUUAGUUUUGAAAGAAAUUGCCAAACUACCUUCCAAAGUGGCAGCAGCUUUUCGCAUUCCCACUAGCAACGAAUGAGAGUUCCUGUUGCUCCACGUCCUCACAUUUGAUGAUGUCAGUGUUCUGGAUUUUGGCCAGCUGAUAGGUAUGUAGUGGUAUCUUGCUGUUUUAUUUUGCAUUUCAUUGAUAACAUAUGACUAGGAGCAUCUUAUGCUGAUUUUUCAUCUGCAUAUCUUCUUUGCUGAAGUGUCUGUUAAGGUAUUUGGCCCAUUUUUUAAUUGGAUUGUUUUCUUAUUGUUGAGUUUUAAGAGUCCUGUGUAUAUUUUGGAUGACAUUUCUUUUUUGUGUGUCUUUUUUUUGGAUGACAUUUCCUUAUCAGAUAAAUAUGUAUCUUGAAAAUAUA